GUUGUUGUGUCCCAGCCUUCCCAAGCUUCCAGGUGUCCCAGAAACCCAGGAAAUCGAGACUCAUGACUCCCAGAGAGGAUGGCAUCUAGAAGUAGACGAUCAAGGGUGGAAUCUACAGUCCGUGAGCCCUGACUUCUUGCCUUCGUCUCAAAUAGACUCUGCAGCCAGCCAUCUAUGCAGCGCCCCAGUGGCUUUGAAAUGCAACAGAAACCAUCACCCCCGGACCGUGGGCUCCAUGCCAGUGGGCAAAGCACAGCCUGGGAAGAAUUGGUUUGCAGCCAGGCAGUCCUCCAUCCAGUCUUGACUUUGGCACUUGUGAUAUGACUUGCACAGACCAAAAAAGUCACUCUCAAAGAGCUCUCGGCACACAGACCCCAGCUUUACAAGGACCCCAGCUCCUUAACACAGAUCCCAGCUCCGAGGAAACUCGUCCCCCCCACGUUAAUCCUGACCGACUUUGCCACAUGGAGCCAGCAAACCAUUUCUGGCAUGCAGGGGACCUCCAAGCAAUGAUAUCCAAGGAAUUCCAUCUGGCAGCCACCCAGGAUGACUGCAGAAAAGGAAGGACACAGGAGGAUAUCCUGGUUCCCUCUUCCCACCCAGAGCUGUUUGCAUCAGUCCUGCCAAUGGCUCCGGAAGAAGCUGCCAGGCUCCAGCAACCUCAGCCCCUUCCUCCUCCCUCAGGAAUCCACCUAUCCGCCUCUAGGACCUUGGCUCCAACUCUAUUGUACUCGUCUCCUCCCUCCCAUUCUCCUUUUGGUCUCAGCUCCUUGAUCUAAGCCUCCCAGAGAGACCCCUAGAACGUUUCCCUCAAGGACCUUUCUGCCUGGAAGUCUGUUAGCCUUUCAGAAGUAACAUGUCCAAAAUAAAAUUUGAUUCCUCCCAGGUUGUUCCCUGCCUGGUCCGCUACCCCACAGUAAGGAACACCUUAUUAUGCAA